AGUUCCGCCCACCUGCCAGAAACGGGGAUCAGGCCUGGUUACCGGGAGUGGGGCGCCCCUCCUCCUUAUCCCCUCCCCUCUUCCCUGUCCCCUUUCACAGCUGGCUGUAGCUGGCCAAGGAGUUCUCGAUUAAAGAGGAAGGGGCAGUGCUCACAUUUCUGGGCAGGUGUCUGGAAAAUAUGAGGGGCCACCCCUCUCUGCUGCUGCUAUAUAUGGCAUUAACCACCUGCCUGGAUACUUCACCCAGUGAGGAGACAGACCAAGUCCUUCCUCUUCCAGGAGUCCAGGACCCAGCCCCUUCCUCCUUCAGACCCAGGAAUCUGGAUUCCCAGCCCCUGCUCCUUCCUCCAGGACCCCACUGCUUUCCAUCCCCCUAUGACUCCAGCCCUAGGGACCCUCCAUUUUUCUGUCCCUCAUGUCUUUGGGUCCAGAAGUCUUCCUGGGUCCCCCAGAGGCCCAGAGCUUCCUGAGUAGCCAUACCCGGAUUCCAAGAGCCAACCACUGGGACCUGGAGCUGCUCACACCAGGGAACCUGGAACGGGAGUGUCUGGAAGAGAGGUGUUCCUGGGAAGAGGCCAGGGAGUAUUUUGAGGACAACACUCUCACGGAGCGCUUUUGGGAGAGCUACAUCUACAAUGGCAAAGGAGGGCGUGGACGAGUGGAUGUGGCCAGCCUGGCUGUGGGGCUGACAGGUGGCAUCCUGCUCAUUGUCCUGGCCGGCCUGGGAGCCUUUUGGUAUCUGCGCUGGCGACAGCACCGAGGCCAGCAGCCCUGUCCCCAAGAGGCCGGGCUCAUUAGCCCUCUGAGUCCUUUGAACCCUCUGGGCCCACCGACGCCCCUGCCUCCACCCCCACCCCCACCCCCAGGCCUCCCCACCUAUGAGCAGGCGCUGGCAGCCUCUGGGGUACACGACGCACCUCCACCCCCCUACACCAGCCUCAGGAGGCCUCACUGAAGAGCUGCUUUCGAGACCCGGCUCUCCGAACCGUGCCCCUGAUUCAUACCGGAUUCCGGAAGCCGCUAGGCCUCAUAGACGCCGAAGCUGGACUUGGAGUGGGGAAUGGUGGGAGUAGGGGUCAUCCGGCCCGAGGCCUGCCCUGGCACACGCGUUUCCGCCGCGUAUGGAUAUACACAUGUUUUCGGCAACGUGUUCCCGUGUCCUGGCCCCUCACGGGCCCCCACACUCUCCUGACCGUGAGGGCACUGGUCAGUUCCGCCCCCGUGGUAGGCAGACGCGCGGGGAAAUUCGGACCCAGGAGCCCAGCCCCGGCUGUGCCAUCUUGUGUAUGGGCAGAUAUGACCUGACAGCCCCCUCCAGUGCCACAGGGUACGCACACGCAGAGCCCCGCCUGUGCACACGCGUGUCUUCGUGCACUCCCCGUGCGGUACAGGGGCACUUCGUAACCCAGGGAAAGGGCGGGGGGCAUAUUUGCAAGCGCGCUCGGUGCGGGCAGGCUCGCAUUGCACCCAGGGAGCUGGAGUUGAGCUGUUCCCCUAAAUAAAAACCCUUCGGAAAGGAGACCAAAAAAAGCAGAAAUAAUGCAAAAAAUAAUAAUGAAAUGAACUGCGA